GCCCGCGCCGCGCGCUCUCCGCGCGCCCCUCCGGAGGGACUGCGGGGCCGCGGCUGGCGUAACCGGGCUCGGAGCCUCCCGGCGGGCCGGCCCCCGCCUCCCCAAGCCGGAGCGAGCGCACACUCUGCGCCCGGGAGUCUGGGGCCACCUGACCCGCGCCCUCCGCCGGGGCACGCGGACACCCAGCAGGGGCACCCUGGCCUGGGCGCGGAGCCCGUGGCCCUUCCCCUCCCAUACAGCCCGGGCACGGGGGCACCUGACGGGGACCGGUGCCCUGGCCGGCCUCCUGCCUCGGCCAUUCCGCGGUCUCUUCGCCCCUGGGCGCAGUCAACUCCAGGGCCUGUGUGAGUCUAAGCAGUUUGUCGUUCUCCACGUUUGGAUUUAUUACAAGCAAAAUGGAAAUCGAAGUUUUCCUGGAAAUAAUCAAAUAAUAAUAAACCUCCAGCGUAGGAAUAGUGGACUUUGGAUCUGCUUUGAGAUGCUGAAGAUGAUGGAAGUCUAUAAGGAACCUAGAGAACAGCCCAUCUUCACCACCCGAGCGCAUGUCUUCCAGAUUGACCCCAACACCAAGAAGAACUGGAUGCCUGCGAGCAAGCAGGCGGUCACCGUUUCCUACUUCUAUGAUGUCACAAGGAACAGCUAUCGGAUCAUCAGUGUGGACGGAGCCAAGGUGAUCAUAAACAGCACAAUCACACCGAAUAUGACCUUCACCAAAACGUCACAGAAGUUUGGGCAGUGGGCCGACAGCAGAGCCAACACAGUGUUUGGUUUGGGGUUUUCCUCUGAGCAGCAGCUGACAAAGUUUGCAGAGAAAUUCCAGGAGGUGAAAGAAGCUGCCAAGAUAGCCAAAGACAAGACGCAGGAGAAAAUCGAGACCUCAAGUAAUCAUUCCCAAGAAUCUGGGCGUGAAACCCCAUCUUCUACUCAGGCAUCCAGUGUCAACGGGACGGACGAUGAAAAGGCCUCUCACGCCGGUCCAGCCAACACACACCUGAAGUCUGAGAAUGACAAGCUGAAGAUUGCCUUGACGCAGAGCGCAGCCAACGUGAAGAAGUGGGAGAUCGAGCUGCAGACCCUUCGGGAGAGCAAUGCACGGCUGACCACAGCACUGCAGGAGUCGGCAGCCAGUGUGGAGCAGUGGAAGAGGCAGUUCUCCAUCUGCCGUGAUGAGAAUGACCGGCUCCGCAACAAGAUUGAUGAGCUGGAAGAACAAUGCAGUGAGAUCAACAGAGAGAAGGAGAAGAACACGCAGCUGAAGAGGAGGAUCGAGGAGCUGGAGGCAGAGCUCCGAGAAAAGGAGACAGAGCUGAAAGAUCUCCGAAAACAAAGUGAAAUCAUACCUCAGCUCAUGUCAGAGUGCGAAUAUGUCUCUGAGAAGCUAGAGGCGGCAGAGAGAGACAAUCAAAACCUGGAAGACAAAGUGCGUUCCUUAAAGACAGACAUUGAGGAGAGCAAAUACCGACAGCGCCACCUGAAGGUGGAGUUGAAGAGCUUCCUGGAGGUGCUGGACGGGAAGAUUGACGACCUGCAUGACUUCCGCCGAGGGCUCUCCAAGCUGGGCACCGAUAACUAGGGCUGGCCGAGGCCCAGGCCCCGCCCUGGCCCUGGAGCAACCUGGACGGUGUUCCCUUGAGCUGGUGUGACGUGCCCUCGUUUAUUCUGACAUCCAGCCCAGUCUCAGUACUGUUGUCAUAACCUUACGCCAGACUCAGGCAGAAUGUAAGCCAUUCACUCGUGAGCAUCGCAGCCGCUUGUGCUGCCUGGAAGCUGCAGGGCCAGGACUGCAUUUUCAGUUUGCAAUUGAGGUCUCCUGAUUUUGGUGUUUCCAAGACUGGCUGCUAUACCUUGAUAAGCUUUCCUUCUGCCUCCAUGAAACCUGGUGUCUAAAAAAGAUCAACUAAAACUUGGAACCCUUUAACCAAGAGGACCUUUAAAAAUAACCUUUCAUUCCAGUCAAGACCCAGCUGGAUGCAUUUUAAAGUUGGGAGUGGCGAGGAAGCCUUCCUAGUGCCGCCCGGGGAAUGUAAAACCACCAGAGCAACAGGUUGGGACAGUAUGGUCAGGCCUUGGAGGGAAAGAGAACCAGUAUCCACACAAGACCUCGAACUUGUGUGGCCCCUCAGUUUCAUCUCUCCUGCCUGCCAUCACAUUAGACUUUAAUUGGGUGAGAGAACAGGGCAGAGACUGUCACCUGCAUUUUGCAGAUGGGAAGUAGAGACAGAGAAAGUGACACGCCCAGGGUCACCCAGCGGUGACCAGCAGCGUGGACUCUGCAUCCAGGUCUCCUGGACCUUGAUGCAGUAUCUUUUGAGACAUGCCACUCUAGUCCCUUUGGUGACCCGUGGGUGCCAAGAGAAAAUAAUUCUUAUAUCCUGAUAAGAGCAUAUUACAAUUAUAUUAUUUCAAUAUGUGUCCACAGCAAAGGACAGUUUACAAAAAUGUGAAUCCGAAUGACAUUUAGGAAUGUUUGUUAUAAAUGAUAAGUUCCACUUUGGAAUGAUUCUGGUUUUGCAGGAAUCUUUCCAAGAAAGUUGGUUAAAAUGAUGUCUCUGCCUGUGAGGCCAGUUCUAUGGAAAACAAACACACCCUGAGUUCUUUAUUGAUGGCUUUAGUGGAGGCAGAGCAGUAUGUUCAAAACAAGUGGGAGGCCCUGAGAUCGCAGGAAUGGAAACAGAGUUCUGGCUGGGGGUGGCCUGUCCACUGCCCGCCCCUUCCUGGAGAUGCACUCCUUUCUGGCUUUCUGGGGAGGGAGCAGCCUUGCUCAGUGGUGGGAGCAGCUUGAACGGGACCUGAUCAACACCCAGGAAGACUGUGCACAGAGGGCAGUUGGUCUCCAGCCUGCAGGCUCCAUGAGCACAGCCUUGAUGGUGGUGGGCAGGCGCCUGCCUGCUGUGGACUACAUUUGAUGCAAAACAUCAAGUAAAGGGUGGAGCGUAAUACAGUGAAUAUGCCUCCCAGAAACAUCAUGCUCUGCCUAUUUUAACAGGGCUCUUUUUCUUUAGAAAAGUCUCCUUCUCUAUAGAAACCAGGGACAAUUUUGGAUGAGAGCCAACCACAGGACGCGCUGGGGACGUUAUGGUGGGACCUCACAUGUGGCCAGGUGCACCUUUGGGAAGAAGGCAGACGUGAUGUGACUUAGCACAGGCACUCAAAAGAGGCAGCCACUGGUCUUUGCUAAUAUCCAGAAGUGGAUUGUUUGUUCCAUUCAUCCUUCUAGAAGCUAAAUUCUUUCAUUGCCUUGAGACAUCACUAGAUUUUGAAGCACUUGCAAACUAGAAGCUUGCAAGAUCAAUGUCCAUGUAUAUUUUUAAAGAUAUGCAUGCUUUAAAAGGACCCUAAUUUCUGAGUACAUGGCUUCCCCAAAGAAACAGUAUAUAUUCUGGAGAUGAUGGGGGUUUUGGCAUGGAGAGGGACUCCUGUCUAGUCUAGAAAAUGUUACUUACAUGCCUCUUCCAUGUACCGAUCUCAAGAAUAUGGGUUUUCUAGUUGGCUUUAAACACUACCCAGGCAGGAAGGUGGCUUUGGUAAGAAUUUUGAGCUGGAUGAAAUGUUCUAGUGAACUUACGACUGUGUAUGUGCGCACGCGUGUGUGUGUGUGUGUGUGUGUGUGUGUGUGUGUGUGUGUGUGAAGAAACAGCAAAAGGGGAAGUGGGAGAAACAGUAAGGAAGCGUUUUUAAUUAAAAAUAUGUAUACCUAAGAGGAGACUUUAUUUUCUAUUUCUGGUGGUGGUGAUCUAUGUUCUGGAAUCCAUUUACCAGAAGUUUGUGGAUCUUUUGUUUGAAGUGGAAUUGUUCAGUGCCCUACUCUCUUUGACGGUGCAGAGCCUUGCGGCAAAGUGUUCUCCUGGGCCCUAGAGACCCCCAGGGCACCUGGCAGGAGCCCGUAAACCACGGCAGAGUCCCAAGUGGUGCAUGUUUUGGCGAGUGAUGGGCAGGACUGAUGAUUCACAGCUGUGAGGCUGUGCUAUUGUUUUUACCCUCUUGUACUGCUUUUAAUAGGAAGUCCCGACUUUACGUCAGUUGUGAGAGCAGCGUCUUAUGAUGUGACAGGCAAGAAGACAUUCCUUGCAUCAAAUAUAAGAGUUUAAUGAGAAGAGUGGAGUGGAUAAGUGAACUCUCCCAAGAGUACUGUUUUUUGUUUCCCUUUUUAAAUGCUUUCUUGGUACAUAAAUAAUAUAAUACUUUUUUUAAAGAAAUUCCAGAUGAGUGGGAAAAAAACCAAUCACCUGUUAUUACACUAUCUGAUUAUAACCACUGUUAACAUUUCAGUUUUUAUCUUUUCAGACUUUUUUCUAUGCAUCUGUGUGUGUUUUAUUACUUUUUCCAUGAAAUAUAAUCAUAUUAUACAUACUGUUUUAUAACUUUUAUCCCUUUUAAUGCUAUAUUGUGAAUAGAUUUCUAUAUCAGUAAAUAUGUAAUUACAUUAUUUUUAACCUCUAUGUAGGUUGUACCUUGGAUACUUAGGUUGUUUCCAAUUUUUUUACUGUUGUAGUCAAGGACAUAAUGAAGUUCUUCUAACAUCCUUGCGAACUUUUCAGAAUAUUGACUUAGGGUAAUUUUCUGAAGUUAUCACUGGCUCAAAAGUACGCGCCUCCCUAUCUGCGGCUCCUUUCCUUCUGAGGCAUACAGGACUUCACCCUCCAUCCCCCUUGUACUCAUUCAGGGUCCUAUGACUAAUUCUGGCCAAUGAAAUGUGAGCACAGGUGACACAUGAAGCUCCAGACAGACACUGAAAUGCCCAUGAGCAGUUCCGCAGUGUCUGCCUUCCCUUCCCUCAGCAAAUGCUGAUGUCCCAGGGACAGAGCCUCUGUCAAGCCUGGAUCCCUGAGUGACUACGUGGAGCAGCCCCCUUCUCCCUUCAUGUUACCCUCACCUGCCACCCUGCAUGGACGGGUAGCAUGAAUAAAAAAAAUAAACCUUAGGUGUUAAACACUGGGGUUUCAGGGUUAAUUGGUUAACUGCAGCAUAACAUAUCCUGUUGCAACAAUAAAAAAGAAUGCACAUUUUUAGGACUUGUAAUAUGUAUUGCCUCAAAUUGCCUUCCAGAAAGACAGACCCAAUUAUACUCCCACCCACAGUGUGUGAGUGUGUACUGCUUCCUCUUUAACACUGGAGUUACCCUGGGGACAGAGAGCUAAAAAAAAUAUUUUUUUGGUUAAAAUGUAACCCUUUAAGGUGUUCAGCAGUAUCAUUGAUUUCUAAGAGGUUUAUUUCAUAAACAUUGUAAAACAAAAUUUUAAGUUGCACGUAUGGCUUUUUAAAAACGUUUAGACAUUUAAAAAAACACCUUUUAGUCAAGUUUAUCUGUUACUUUUUUUUUUUUUUUUAAUGGUUGCUACCUAUGCCGUCAUGCUUAUGCAGGUCUUUCCAAUUCUUUUUUUUUUUUUUUUUUUUUUUUUUUUUUGAGACGGGGUCCACCCUGGCCCCCAGGCUGGAGUGCAGUGGCGUGAUCUCAGCUCACUGCAACCUGCGCCUCCCGGGUUCAAGCGAUUCUCAUGUGUCAACCUCCCUCCUGAGUAGCUGGGACUACAAGUGUAUGCCACCACGCCCAGGUAACUUUUUGUUUUUAGUAGAGAUGGGUUUCGCCAUGUUGCCUAGGCUGGUCUCGAACUCCUGAACUCAGGCAAUCCACACGCCUUGGCCUCCCAAAGUGCUGGAAUUACAGGUGUGAGCCACCAAGCCCGGCGAGGUCUUCCCAAUUCUGAUGGCAAGGUUGUAUAAAUAUUCACCACUAUCUUAUUCUUGUACUUUUAUUAUUUCUUUCUAAACAGUUAAAUCUGUGAUCUGGCUGGGCGUGUUGGCUCUUGCCUGUAAUCCCAACACUUUGGGUCGCCAAGGUGGAAGGAUCACUUGAGUCCAGGCAUUUGAGGUUACAGUGAGCUUUGAUGGCACCGGUGCACUCCAGCCUGGGGAACAGAGCAAGACCCUGUCUCUAAAAAAAAUUUUAAAAACCUCUGAUCUAUCUGGAAUGUAUUUUCUAAAUUACCCCAACACUGUUUAUUGGGAAGUCUGUCCUUUAUUCUAUAUGAAAUCCCAUUUUUGCCAUACACCUAGUAGCCCUUCUGUUGGGUGCCAGGAUAAGCACCCUGGCCUUGAGUGUGCUGUGAACUCUUUAUUAUGGGUUGUGAUCUUCCUGCACAUUCUAGCACUGGUACCACAUUGUUUGGAUCGCCAUAGCUUUGGACUAAACUUCCCCAUUAAACUUUUUCAAAACUUGCCUAGUAUAUUGUGCAGGCCGGGCAUGGUGGCUCACGCCUGUAAUCCCAGCACUUUGGGAGGCCAAGGUGGAUGGAUCACCUGAGAUCAGGAGUUCGAGACCAGCCUGGAUAACAUGGCGAAACCCCAUCUCUACUAAAAAUACAAAAAAAAAAAAAAAAAAAAAAAAUUAGCUGGCUGUGGUGAUAGGAACCUGUAAUCUCAGCUACUUGGGAGGCUGAGGCAGUGAACCCAGGAGGCAGAGGUUGCAGUGAGCUGAGAUAGCACCAGCCUGGGCAACGGAGCGAGACUCUGUCUCAAAAAAACAAAAAACAAAACAAAAAAAAAACCUUCCAAAAGAAGUUUGAGAUAAUUUUAUGUUUAGAAAAAUUAGAAAUUGGAUUGAGUAAAAUUUACAUAUUUUACACAAGAGGACUAACAUCUUUAUAAUAUUUAACCUUUCAGUAAAUUUAUGUUUUAUGUUUCUCAGCCUAUCUUUUCUAGUAUAGGUGAUUUUUUUAGUGUGGUUACUAUUGUAAAUGAGAUCCUACUACUUUAAAAAAUGAAAAUUAAAUCUAUCGCUUUUAUGACUUUAAAACAUUAGACUUAUGUAAGUGUAAACAUUAUUUAAAAACAUAAUGUAGAAAAUUAAAGUCCCCCAUAAUUAAAAUCCCUUUCCCCCAGAAAAAGUCAACAGCAUAUUCAUCAGUUUUUUCCUAAAGUAUGUUUUAGCACUUUGACCAUAUGAGACAACCCUUCUGCUGUUAGCAUUUUUCUCUUUGCAAUAGAUCUUCCUAUGUCAGUACACAUCAAUCUACCUCAUUCUUACCUCUGCAUAAGAGAGUAGUGUGUAGUUGUAUAAUAGUUUAACUUGGCGAUUGGUUAUUGAUUUUGUAACUAGCCAGUUACUGAAUUAUUCUAAAGGUUUUGCUGUUGUUAAUUUCUUUCGCCUUUUUCAGUUGGGUAAUAGUUCUGGGUAGGUUGAUAAUUUUAUUCCCAUAUUUGUAAUCUUAUUUCACUUUCUCAACUCAUCACAUUGACUGGUACUUUUAGAACAAUGUUAAAAAACAUUUACAUAAUUGUGCUGAUAUUGUACAUUAUUUGAUAUAUAUAUAUCAAAUUUUUUUUACUUAGAAGAGUGUUUCUCCAAAACUAUAAAUUUGACUCUUAGUGUAAAAUAAUCUUAAUAUUUGAAUUAUACAUUCAGGUUAUGCCCUCUAUUUCUAGUUUGAUGAAAAUAUUAUUAGUAAUGGAUGUUGGGGUUUUAUUAAAUGGCUUUUUUCCACAUCUGUCAAGAUGAUCAACUGGCUUUUCUCUAUUAUGACUUUAGAUGAAUCGUUUUAAUAGAUUUGCUAAUGUUAAGACAUCUCUGCAUUUCUACAAGAAUCUGAUGUAGUCAUAGUAUACUAUUCUUUUAAUAUACAUCUCCUUUCAAUGUUAACAGUGGUUAUUUAUGAUUGGUUGGUCCAUAGUAGAUUUUUAUUUUGUGUUUCUUAUCUGUACUUUCUGAUUUUUCUACAAAGAUUGUGUAUUACUUGUAUAAUAAAAAUAAGAGCUUUAAAUUGUGAAA